AGAAAUCCCUUAGCUUACCACAGAGCAGAACCCCCAGAGGACCAGGACUCCCAAUGUCCCCCCAUUCCCCACCCGCCAGGAGAGAGCUUACCUCUCCCUCUUCCCAGCUGAGACCCUUCUGUGUCCCUUUCUGCACCUCUGCCCCGCCGCCCCCUCUAGCUCUCAUGCCUUCAUAUUUCCCCUGCCUUACUCCUCCUUUCCACCCAGCUCAGCCCUGUCCUUCCUAAACCCUCCUUCAGGCUUGGUGUCUUUCAGUAGCCAAAUAAAUUUCAGAGCACGGAGAUGGGAGCCAGCACAGAUGAGGUCCAGGCAUUUUUUAAGGGGUAGAGUGAGAUCAGGAGUCACCCUGUUUCUUCCCUCCCCACCCAGACUCCACACAGCCCUGGGCUGUGAAUCACUGAUUCAAAAGGGCCAUGAAGUUAGGCAAAGGUGCAGAACUGUUAUGGGGCUGGAGGAACAUGCAGGUGGCAUGAGGGCCAUUUGGGUGACAGCAAGAGGAAGCAGCGCUGCUCACUCCUUCUCCAGUCCAGGGCCCCGUGAUGGAUUUCACCUUGGACAUUUGCCUUUGGAACGGUUGCUCCUUGCCAAGAGCACUCCCCCAGAGACAGAUGGAGAAGGAGACAGCUCCGUGGUUCCCGUUCUGGGACUGGCCUUUUGCCUCCUGCCUCCCACAGCUCAGGUGGAGAGAGGAGGGCCCUGCCCUUACCGACUGGAGAGCAUCAGGCUCUCUGGACAAUGCAGCUCAGCCUUCAGCUCCACCAGAGAGGCUGCAGUGUGUGAAGACAGCUCAUUCUGCGGGAGGAGGAAGAGCAGAGAAACCACCACCCUAUGGGUCGUUCUCAGAUCCCUCGUGUGCUGGCUGUCUCCCACCCAGGCUCAGUUUGCACUGCUAAUCUGUUACGUCUUUCUUGGGCAGCUGUUGUGGAGCCUGGUCCAUCCUGAGCACUCCAGUGUUCCAUUUCAAGGAUCUCUUCCUGGCUCCCCUCCCACCAGAGAAUGUGGCCUUGGGAUCAAGGCGUGGAGAGCUGCCAGCUACUGCCACCUGCCACAAAGCCUCAUCACCCUUGCGUAUCUCUCUCCCCUCUCCGUCCUCGGCAUGGGGUCACAUUGUGGGUCAUUAUUUCCUUUCACCAAGGUAUGAGCAGAGGGAGAGAGGGCUGGAAAAAGAGACUCUCCCUUUGCUAACUGAUGAGGGAGAAGUAUGGGGUCCAAGUGGGCCUGCCCCUUGCCUAAUUUUUGCCCAAUUUUUUGGCCUCUGGAGUCCCUGGUAGACUUCUUAACUUCUUGCACACAAGGUUACCAUGUGUCUAAUUGCUCAGCUCCAGUUAGAGUGGUGGAGGGAAACUGGUAUCAAUGAAUGAAUGAAUGAAUGGAUGGAUGGUUUAAUGACAGCUUGGAGAACCGACUGGGGUUUGAGCAAGAAACAGGAAGAGAAAGCCAACAUCUUUUAGCUCACCAAAUACUUUCAUGCCCCUUGGGAGGAAGAAAAAUGGAUAUGGGAAAUGCAGAGCAUGGAAGAGCUUAAAUUGAGCAUAAAGGACAUAAAACUAGAUAAGUAAGAUCAGAAAUAAAAGAUGAGUCAUCAUCGAA